GGCCCCACCCCGGCGGCGCAGCCCGCCCGCCCGCGCGUCCCUCGGUCCACCUGCAGCAGGGAGGAAGACAGGCAAUCCCUCCGGCUGUCCGACCAAGAGAGGCCGGCCGAGCCCGAGGCUUGGGCUUUUGCUUUCUGGCGGAGGGAUCUGCGGCGGUUUAGGAGGCGGCGCUGAUCCUGGGAGGAAGAGGCAGCUACGGCGGCGGCGGCGGUGGCGGCUAGGGCGGCGGCGAAUAAAGGGGCCGCCGCCGGGUGAUGCGGUGACCGCUGCGGCAGGCCCAGGAGCUGAGUGGGCCCCGGCCCUCAGCCCGUCCCGCCGGACCCGCUUUCCUCAACUCUCCAUCUUCUCCUGCCGACCGAGAUCGCCGAGGCGGCCUCAGGCUCCCUAGCCCCUUCCCCGUCCCUUCCCCGCCCCCGUCCCCGCCCCGGGGGCCGCCGCCACCCGCCUCCCACCAUGGCUCUGAAGAGAAUCCACAAGCUCCCUCCACAAAACCGCCUGAGCUCGGGCUGACAGAGGAAGCCGUUUUGCCCGAUCCACAAGUAUAUCCUGAGUUCACUUACCUCUUGGGUGGCAGCACACAUCGGUCCACCCUGCUUGUCCAGAAACUGUUAAGAGUUGGAAGUUCAGAAGAAAAAAAAAAGGAAUUGAAUGAUCUGGCACGGGACCCUCCAGCACAGUGUUCAGCAGGUCCUGUUGGAGAUGAUAUGUUCCAUUGGCAAGCUACAAUAAUGGGGCCAAAUGACAGUCCCUAUCAGGGUGGAGUAUUUUUCUUGACAAUUCAUUUCCCAACAGAUUACCCCUUCAAACCACCUAAGGUUGCAUUUACAACAAGAAUUUAUCAUCCAAAUAUUAACAGUAAUGGCAGCAUUUGUCUUGAUAUUCUACGAUCACAGUGGUCUCCAGCACUAACUAUUUCAAAAGUACUCUUGUCCAUCUGUUCUCUGUUGUGUGAUCCCAAUCCAGAUGAUCCUUUAGUGCCUGAGAUUGCUCGGAUCUACAAAACAGAUAGAGAAAAGUACAACAGAAUAGCUCGGGAAUGGACUCAGAAGUAUGCGAUGUAAUUAAAGAAAUUAUUGGAUAACCUCUACAAAUAAAGAUAGGGGAACUCUGAAAGAGAAAGUCCUUUUGAUUUCCAUUUGACUGCUUUCUAUGAGCCCACGCCUCAUCUUCCCCUGUGCACAUGUUUACCUGAUACAGCAGUGCUGCGUGUUGUACAUACUUGGAACAACAAACUAGAAAUACUGUACUUCUGUACCAACAUUGCCUCCUAGCAGAGAAGUGUGUGUGUGACAAGCCAGUUCUACAGGCAUUACCUAGGUGUGAGACUAAAAGCUUUUCUUAUUGACUUAAAUUUGGAUAACAGCAAGGUGUGAGGGGGGUGGUGGGUAUGGUGUGUGCUUGGAUGGGAAAGAAAAGGCUCCACUCACCUAUAGGAGAUUAUUUUUAAGUGGAAUCCAUUUAAACUCAAAACAGUUAUGAAAAGCAAGGUGAAGAACAUGAAGCUGUGUCUGUAUUCAUUUUAUUCCGAAGGAGCUACGUCUUAGGUGAAAGUUAUGACCAACCAGAUUAAACUCUACCCACAUCCUGCAUUUUAAGGUCUAAGUUUAACUGGUCAACAUUUAAAUGGAUUGGAGCUAUUAGUACAUCAAGUGUGAUGGGCUUUGUUCCCAACUCUUUUACAUCUCCCUACCCCUUCAACCUUUGGCCUUUCAGCCCUUCUUUCUCUCUUCCAUAUUCUUUGGUUUGUAUGUGGUUUCUCAGUUAAUACAUAGCUAAUAGCUCUUAUUUUUCUUAUGUUUUUAACCGCUUAGGUCUAUUUGGAUGUAAGGGUGAAAAUUCAUUUGAUGGAAAUACUUGUGUAUAUUUAAAGACCCAAUUGCUCCUCUGGAGCUUGUACUUUCAAGAAUGAUUAAUCUGUGUAAUAAACUGGUUACUACAGUCAUUACAUAUAAUUUUGUGUGAAUAGGCUUUUUCAUUUUUAAGAAGUUUGUCUAGCUGAGAUUAGUGGUGGAUUUUCUCCCACUUCUGAAAUGUUCAUUUAUACUGGUUGCAUUUUAAGAUCAUGAAACAAUUCCAGUUACAUUGUAAAAAGGAUAUCUUACGAGUAAUUUUAUUGAACAAGUUAGAGGCAUAAGCUUAAGAGCAUUUCCAUGAAACAACACAUGCAGCAUUCCAGGAACUUGAUUGUUAAAUUCAAUAAGAAAUUUGCUUUAUUAAUGAAACUAAGCUGCAUUUCAUCAAAACCUUGUGACAUUCCCUUGGUACAUAGGACAUAAAACACAGAGGCAUUGCUAUUUGGUAAGUUAAGCUUCUGUGAUUGUAAUUAUAAAAGAGCAACAUUGACCAAACCUGGGAAACAAGAGCACAGUCUUGUUUGGAGAGUCUACAUAAUUACUUUGCACUAACAUUUGCAGGAUGUUCACACAAUUUUAAAUUGUACUGUAUGUGGCUUUUUGAAGUCUUCCCUUGACCCUAGUAAAAUAUAGCUUGAAACUUGUAAACAACUGUGUUUGCCAGAAACAUCAUUCAUGUGAACUAGGCAAGUUACCUUUUUUCCCCCCUUCUUUUCCUAAUUGUAAACUAGGCCAACCUGAAAGCCAUGGCUGAUGCUCUAGCCAUCAGGUUCUUUCAAAUGCAUCUUUACACUCUUGCACAAAAGUUAAGGAAUAAAUGUCCACUGCUUUUGGUUUUAAA